AGGACUGGUGUUAAGGGUCACGCAAGAUGGCGGCGCCCAGAGGCUGCUGAGGCGCGGAACGGAGGAUGGCGCUGGUGGCGUUGGUGGCUGGGGCUCGGCUGGGGCGGCGGCUGAGCGGGCCGGGGCUGGGGCGAGGGCACUGGACGGCGGCCGGGCGCUCCCGGAGCCGGCGCGAAGCGGCAGAAGCCGAGGCGGAGGUGCCCGUGGUCCAGUACGUGGGCGAGCGCGCUGCCCGCGCCGAUCGCGUCUUCGUGUGGGGCUUCAGCUUCUCGGGGGCGCUGGGCGUGCCUUCCUUUGUGGUGCCCAGCUCCGGGCCCGGGCCCCGCGCCGGCGCCCGACCGCGCCGCAGGAUCCAGCCCGUGCCCUAUCGCCUGGAGCUGGACCAAAAGGUGCAGGCCGCGGCUUCCUCCUUCUCUCCUUCUCUCUCUUCCGCGCUCCCGGCCUCCCUCGACCUGUUCGGCUCUCUUCAAGAAGUUGGCUCCUCUGGGUGGACAGACUUCCGGCAGGACGACCCUCGAGCUGGCUGCAAGCCCAGGAGGGGAAGGCGUUAGGGGUGGCCAUCAACAUUUAUUGGGUGGCAGUGCCAGAUGUUGUGCCGGGUCGUGUCAUUCGCUUAGCACCCAAUUUCAUCUGCUGCUUGCGGCUAUGGAUUCACACUGCUGUCCUCUAAGACUGCGGAUGUUACGAAAGUCUGGGGGAUGGGACUCAACAAAGAUUCUCAGCUUGGAUUUCACAGGAGCCGGAAAGAUAAAACGAGGGGCUACGAGUAUGUGUUGGAGCCCUCACCCGUCUCCCUGCCUCUGGACAGACCUCAGGAGACACGGGUGCUGCAGGUCUCCUGCGGCCGAGCUCACUCUCUUGUGUUGACUGACAGGGAAGGAGUCUUCAGCAUGGGAAACAAUUCUUAUGGGCAAUGUGGAAGAAAGGUGGUCGAAAAUGAAAUUUACAGUGAAAGUCACAGAGUCCACAGGAUGCAGGACUUCGAUGGCCAGGUGGUCCAGGUCGCCUGUGGUCAGGAUCAUAGUCUGUUCCUGACGGAUAAAGGAGAAGUCUAUUCUUGUGGAUGGGGUGCUGAUGGGCAAACAGGUCUGGGUCACUACAAUAUCACCAGCUCGCCCACCAAGCUGGGUGGAGACCUGGCGGGAGUGAACGUUAUCCAAGUUGCCACCUACGGUGAUUGCUGCCUGGCCGUGUCCGCCGACGGAGGACUUUUUGGUUGGGGAAACUCGGAGUACCUGCAGCUGGCCUCUGUCACUGACUCCACACAGGUGAAUGUGCCCCGCUGCUUACACUUCUCAGGAGUGGGGAAGGUGCGACAGGCUGCAUGCGGUGGCACGGGCUGUGCAGUGUUAAACGGAGAAGGACAUGUUUUUGUCUGGGGCUAUGGAAUUCUUGGGAAAGGUCCAAACCUAGUGGAAAGUGCCGUCCCUGAAAUGAUUCCACCCACUCUCUUUGGCUUGACGGAGUUCAACCCAGAAAUCCAGGUUUCCCGCAUCCGAUGUGGACUCAGCCACUUUGCUGCACUGACCAACAAAGGAGAGCUGUUUGUAUGGGGCAAGAACAUCCGAGGGUGCCUGGGAAUCGGUCGCCUGGAGGACCAGUAUUUCCCAUGGAGGGUGACGAUGCCUGGGGAGCCUGUGGACGUGGCAUGUGGCGUGGACCACAUGGUGACCCUGGCCAAGUCAUUCAUCUAAACCUCCCUCACCUGCUUGGGCGGCCCCGUCCCGGGAACCACUGGCACUCCUUGGCAGAGGCCAGCGCGUGGCCAGCCCCCCGGGGUUCUUGGAUGGUGGUGGCGGAGGACCCUGCGUGCAGUGUGACGCUCUGUCCUGAAUCCCUUAGCGGGUACCUACCAGGAGGAUCAGGGCAAGGUCCCUCUCCAGCUGCAGGUGAGGCCUGCGGAACUCAGCUUGGAUGGCAGCCUUUGGUGGGCCGCUGUGGCCCGCACGUCUCUGUUCUCUCCAAGUAACAUGCGACGGUGUCUGGUGUCACGUCUCGCCUGAGAAGCCCGUCUUAGGAAAGCUUAGCUUGAACACAGUGCUCGGGAGGUUUCUGCUCUGUCUGUCAUGGCAGUCUCUUGGUUUGUGUCUGGCCAAGGCCAUGCGUGUGCCUCGGACCGAGCCCCAGCUUAGGCGAGGGAGUCAGGCUGGCUUCGGCCCUCGGUUUUCAUUCAGGCCACCCUGCUCAUGGCCCUUCCUGGCCGCCUGCCACACCGCAAGCUCGCUGGGGGGACACUAGAAGCACCGUGGCCUGGGAUUCCAUCUGGAGCUGUCCGCAGGCACCAGCCCCAGCCUCCCACCACGCUCACUGCCUGGCUUGGAAAAGUUAAGAAGCCCCUCAGGAAGAGAAUCGAGGCCAAGUUCCUCUGCGCCGAGGGCCCCGAGCAUAUCCGCCAAGGCUCAGCUGCAGUGCCAGGCGGAGGAGGAAGAUCCAGAAAUUGUGAACAAUGUUUGAUUUAGUAGCGUGACUUGCCUUUCCCUUUAAAAACAUCUUUUACAAAUCUGUCUUGGAAUAAAGUCUAUUUUCUGCCUUUUGGUUUUUAA